AGCUCGCUGUUCGCUUCGCUGCCUGACAGCUGCCCUGCCGCCACCAGGCAGUCCCAGCUUCCCCAAACCAGUCUUCUGGCCUCUGUGGCGCCCCAGGCCCGCGGGAUUCAGGGAUUAGGAUCUGGAAGGGUUUGGUCCAAUCCCCUAUCCCUCUCAGCGUCCUGGGCUCACCUCCCCGGCAGCUUAGCGCUCCUCUUCCAAAACUGCUUGCUGUUCUCAGCGGCCAUUGCUCUGGCCGGGGGAAGUCCUUGUAGGCGGGCCAAGGGUUUGCCCGGCGAGAUGCCCCCAGACCCCGCAAUCUGAGGGCCAACCCAGGCCGCUUCCCCGCCGCCGGUCACCCGCUCCCAGCUCCUGGGGACGCCAUCUUGGAUGUGGGCACCCCUCCACCCAGCACCGCUGCCAUUGGUGAGCUGCGCAAGCCGUGGACGGGCCGACCAAUUGGGAGCCGGAAUCCUGCAGGCCGCUGAAGCCGACCGGUAACGUCAGGGGCUGGGCACACAGGUGGACGGGGAAGGCGGAGCUUGGACGAGCCGAGAGGCGGGGCUCAAAGUUCCUACCCGCGAGAGGGAAGAAGCAGGUAAGGAGGUCUCAGCAUGAAACAGCAGCAGUGGUGUGGGAUGACUGCCAAAAUGGGCACCGUGUUGUCAGGGGUCUUCACCAUCAUGGCCGUAGACAUGUAUCUCAUCUUUGAACAGAAGCACCUAGGGAAUGGCAGUUGCACUGAGAUCACACCAAAGUACAGGGGUGCAAGUAACAUCAUAAAUAACUUCAUCAUCUGCUGGAGUUUUAAAAUCGUCCUCUUCCUGUCUUUCAUCACCAUCCUCAUCAGCUGCUUCCUCCUGUACUCAGUGUAUGCCCAGAUCUUCAGGGGCCUGGUCAUCUACAUUGUCUGGAUUUUUUUCUAUGAAACUGCAAACGUCGUAAUACAAAUCCUCACCAACAAUGACUUUGACAUUAAAGAGGUCAGAAUCAUGCGCUGGUUUGGCUUGGUGUCUCGUACAGUCAUGCACUGUUUCUGGAUGUUCUUUGUCAUCAACUAUGCCCACAUAACCUACAAAAACCGGAGCCAGGGCAAUAUAAUUUCCUACAAGAGACGAAUUUCUACAGCGGAGAUUCUCCACAGCAGAAAUAAAAGAUUAUCAAUUUCGAGUGGGUUCAGUGGCUCACACCUGGAAUCCCAGUACUUUGAGAGGCAGAGGUAGGUGGAUCGCCUGAGGUCAGGAGUUCAAGACCAGCCUGGCCUUGGCAGCCAUGGCAAAACCCCGUCUCUACUAAAAAAAAUAGAAAAUUAGCCAGGCGUGGCGGCACACACCUGUAAUCCCAGCCACUUGAGAGGCUGAGACUGGAGAAUCACUUGACCUGGGAGGUGGAGGUUGCAGUGAGCCGAGAUUGCGCCAGUGCACUUCAGCCUGAGUGACAGAGUAAGACUCUGUCCCCCAAAAAAAAAAAAAAAAGUUAGCAGCUUUAUCCACCACUAUAAGCAAUCAUGUUGGCCCUUUUCUUUCCCAUAAGAGGUAGGUCUCUCAGAUUCCCAGGGUAGUUCUAUUUCCUUUUUUCCCCCCACUUUUGCUUAGCAGUUCUGCAAGUAGAGACCCUACUGCCACUCUUUCAGGAGAACAUGAAGAGAAAAUGUGAUUAUAAUCACAACCGGAACAUCCUGCUCAUUGAGGGUAUUUAGUUAAAGGAUAUUGUGAUUUAUCAAAACUUCUGUGAACUCACCUUUCUACCACCUGAUUGGUCAAAAUGAAUGGAAUAAGAUGAAGCUGAAUUGCAGUAGGGCAAUCCUUUUUUCUUGGCAUCUUCAUUAGCCUUCAACCCACAACUCUUUAAUUUAACCCUGGGAUAAGCAAAUCUGUAUUUAUACCAGAUUUUUGCAGCACAAAGGAUACUGUUGGCCCUGGGGUGGGUUUGUGCUAUGAUUUCCCCACUGUGUCUUCUGUUUUAUUCCAGAUAAGAAAAAGAAUAAAAAUAGAGAAAAUUCAUCCUUCAAUUUAUGUCUCGAAUUUCCCCACCCUUUCCAAAUUUGUCAAGGAGUGUGAAAGGCACUUCCUUAAUCAAAGAUAUAUGUUAAACAUACUUCUGUAUCUGUUGCUGUGCUGUACUCUGUAGUGUGAACACUGUACUGAACAUUGUGUAUAUACUGUAUACAAAAAUGUGUAAGAUAUGAAUGACUAUGAGAAUUUUGUAGUUUAGUGGAAGAAAGUAAAUUAUUGUUUAUGAAUCAAUUAGCCAAUCAUAUAAGACAGUAUAUGAUUACAUACUAUCACAAAUAAACAGACAUCACUUUGCAUUCAGGUCCAGAGACUGUAUGAAGCACAUUUUUUAUUUUUGAGACCGAGUCUGGCUCUGUCGCCCAGGCCAGAGUGCAAUGGUGCGACCUCGGCUCACUGCAACCCCCGCCUCCCGGGUUUAAGCGAUUCUCCAGCUUCAGCCUCCUGAAUAGCUGGGAUUACAGGCACAGGCCACCAUGCCUGGCUAAUUUUUGUAUUUUUAGUAGAGACGGGGUUUCCCCAUGUUGGUCAGGCUGGUAUUGAAUUCCUGACCUUAGGUGAUCCACUUGCCUCAGCCUCCCAAAGUGCUGGGAGUACAGGUGUGAGUCACCCACUGCUGCUAUAAUAACUGAGUAAUUUAUAAAGAGCUGAGAUUUAUUUUCUCACACUUUUGGAGGCUAGAAGUUCAAUAUCAAGGUGCCAGUAGGUUUGGUGUCUGGUAAGGGCCUGCUCUCUUUGCUUCUAAGAUGGUGCAAACACUGUCCUUACAUGGCAGAAGGGAUGGAGAGGCAAAAGAAACUAGCUAGUUCCCUCCUGUCCCUUUAUAAGGUCACUUAUUCCAUUCAUGAGGGCUCUGCCCCUAUGAUUCAAUCACCUCCUAAAGGCCCCAUCUUUUAAUGCUGUUGCAUUAGGGAUUAAGUUUCAACAUGAAUUUUGAAGGGGACAGUCAAACCACAGCACUCACCAUUUGGCAAGCUGUCCUUGUCAUUGUCUUCCCCGCUCCCAUCCUCAGGGCUCUCCUGCCUCUGUGCUCCUCGCCUCAGAGGAUGGGCUGUCCUCCAUCCAGGUGCUCAUCCCAGACUCCUUCUUCCACAGCCCCAGGCCCCAAAUCUGUCCCCCAACAUCCCUCUGCUGCCUUACUUCACCUUAUUUCCUUCCAUAGCCUCUCAACUGCUCUGCCUACCUCCACCUUUGCUCCCUUUCUGACCCAUGGCCCUCACAGCAGCAAGAAAGAUUUUUCUAAAAUGCAAAUCGGGCCAGGCGCAGGGGCUCACGUCUGUAAUCCCAAUACUUUUGGAGGCCAAAGCGGGCGGAUCACUUGAGGUCAGGAGUUCAAGACCAGCCUGGCCAACAUGGUGAGACCCCUUCUCUACUAAAACUACCAAAAUUAGGCGGGUAUAGUGGCAGGCACCUGUAAUCCCAGCUACUCGGGAGGCUGAGGCAGGAGAAUUGCUUGAACUUGGGAGAUGGAGGUUGCAGUGAGCCAUAAUUGCACCACUGCACUGCAGCCUGGGCAACAGAGUGAGACUUUGUCUCAAAAAUAAAUAAAUAAAUAAAUAAAAUUCAAAUCUGA